CACACCCUGUGUGUCUCUCUGUCCUGCCAGCACUGAGGGCUCAUCCCUCUGCAGAGCGCCGGGUCACCGGGAGGAGACGCCAUGACGCCCGCCCUCACAGCCCUGCUCUGCCUUGGGCUGAGUCUGGGCCCCAGGACCCGCAUGCAGGCAGGGCCCUUCCCCAAACCCACCCUCUGGGCUGAGCCAGGCUCUGUGAUCAGCUGGGGGAGCCCCGUGACCAUCUGGUGUCAAGGGAGCCUGGAGGCCCAGGAGUACCAACUGGAUAAAGAGGGAAGCCCAGAGCCCUGGGACAGAAAUAACCCACUGGAACCCAAGAACAAGGCCAGAUUCUCCAUCCCAUCCAUGACACAGCACCAUGCAGGGAGAUACCGCUGCCACUAUUACAGCUCUGCAGGCUGGUCAGAGCCCAGCGACCCCCUGGAGCUGGUGAUGACAGGAUUCUACAACAAACCCACCCUCUCAGCCCUGCCCAGCCCUGUGGUGGCCUCAGGGGGGAAUAUGACCCUCCGAUGUGGCUCACAGAAGGGAUAUCACCAUUUUGUUCUGAUGAAGGAAGGAGAACACCAGCUCCCCCGGACCCUGGACUCACAGCAGCUCCACAGUGGGGGGUUCCAGGCCCUGUUCCCUGUGGGCCCCGUGACCCCCAGCCACAGGUGGAGGUUCACAUGCUAUUACUAUUAUACAAACACCCCCUGGGUGUGGUCCCACCCCAGUGACCCCCUGGAGAUUCUGCCCUCAGGCGUGUCUAGGAAGCCCUCCCUCCUGACCCUGCAGGGCCCUGUCCUGGCCCCUGGGCAGAGCCUGACCCUCCAGUGUGGCUCUGAUGUCGGCUACGACAGAUUUGUUCUGUAUAAGGAGGGGGAACGUGACUUCCUCCAGCGCCCUGGCCAGCAGCCCCAGGCUGGGCUCUCCCAGGCCAACUUCACCCUGGGCCCUGUGAGCCGCUCCUACGGGGGCCAGUACAGGUGCUAUGGUGCACACAACCUCUCCUCCGAGUGGUCGGCCCCCAGUGACCCCCUGGACAUCCUGAUCACAGGACAGAUCUAUGACACCGUCUCCCUGUCAGCACAGCCGGGCCCCACAGUGGCCUCAGGAGAGAACGUGACCCUGCUGUGUCAGUCACGGGGGUAUUUUGACACUUUCCUUCUGACCAAAGAAGGGGCAGCCCAUCCCCCACUGCGUCUGAGAUCAAUGUACGGAGCUCAUAAGUACCAGGCUGAAUUCCCCAUGAGUCCUGUGACCUCAGCCCACGCGGGGACCUACAGGUGCUACGGCUCACGCAGCUCCAACCCCCACCUGCUGUCUUUCCCCAGUGAGCCCCUGGAACUCAUGGUCUCAGGACACUCUGGAGGCUCCAGCCUCCCACCCACAGGGCCGCCCUCCACACCUGGAGGUCCUGAGGACCAGCCCCUUAACCCCCCAGGGUCAGGCCCUCAGAAUGGUCUGGGAAGAUACCUGGAGGUUUUGAUUGGGGUCUCGGUGGCCUUCGUCCUGCUGCUCUUCCUCCUCCUCUUCCUCCUCCUCCGACGUCAGCGUCACAGCAAACACAGGACAUCUGACCAGAGAAAGACUGAUUUCCAGCGUCCUGCAGGGGCUGCGGAGACAGAGCCCAAGGACAGGGGCCUGCUGAGGAGGUCCAGCCCAGCUGCUGACGUCCAGGAAGAAAACCUCUCAGAUGCUGCUGUGAAGGACACACAGUCUGAGGACAGGGUGGAGCUGGACAGUCAGCAGAGCCCACACGAUGAAGACCCCCAGGCAGUGACGUAUGCCCCGGUGAAACACUCCAGUCCUAGGAGAGAAAUGGCCUCUCCUCCCUCCUCACUGUCUGGGGAAUUCCUGGACACAAAGGACAGACAGGUGGAAGAGGACAGGCAGAUGGACACUGAGGCUGCUGCAUCUGAAGCCUCCCAGGAUGUGACCUACGCCCAGCUGCACAGCUUGACCCUUAGACGGAAGGCAACUGAGCCUCCUCCAUCCCAGGAAGGGGAACCUCCAGCUGAGCCCAGCAUCUACGCCACUCUGGCCAUCCACUAGCCCGGGGGGUACGCAGACCCCACACUCAGCAGAAGGAGACUCAGGACUGCUGAAGGCACGGGAGCUGCCCCCAGUGGACACCAGUGAACCCCAGUCAGCCUGGACCCCUAACACAGACCAUGAGGAGACGCUGGGAACUUGUGGGACUCACCUGACUCAAAGAUGACUAAUAUCGUCCCAUUUUGGAAAUAAAGCAACAGACUUCUCAACAAUCAA